GCCACUGCCCGUCCGCUCUUCAGCAGCCGGUCGCGGGCGGUGGAAAAGCGAGUGAAGAGAGCGCGACGGCGGCGGCGGCGGCGGCGCAGCUAUUGCUGGACGGCCAGUGGGAGAGCGAGGCCUGAGCCUCUGCGUCUAGGAUCAAAAUGGUUUCAAUCCCAGAAUACUAUGAAGGCAAGAACGUCCUCCUCACAGGAGCUACCGGUUUUCUAGGGAAGGUGCUUCUGGAAAAGUUGCUGAGGUCUUGUCCUAAGGUGAAUUCAGUAUAUGUUUUGGUGAGGCAGAAAGCUGGACAGACACCACAAGAGCGAGUGGAAGAAGUCCUUAGUGGCAAGCUUUUUGACAGAUUGAGAGAUGAAAAUCCAGAUUUUAGAGAGAAAAUUAUAGCAAUCAACAGCGAACUCACCCAACCUAAACUGGCUCUCAGUGAAGAAGAUAAAGAGGUGAUCAUAGAUUCUACCAAUAUUAUAUUCCACUGUGCAGCUACAGUAAGGUUUAAUGAAAAUUUAAGAGAUGCUGUUCAGUUAAAUGUGAUUGCAACGCGACAGCUUAUUCUCCUUGCACAACAAAUGAAGAAUCUGGAAGUGUUCAUGCAUGUAUCAACAGCAUAUGCCUACUGUAAUCGCAAGCAUAUUGAUGAAGUAGUCUAUCCACCACCUGUGGAUCCCAAGAAGCUGAUUGAUUCUUUAGAGUGGAUGGAUGAUGGCCUAGUAAAUGAUAUCACGCCAAAAUUGAUAGGAGACAGACCUAAUACAUACAUAUACACAAAAGCAUUGGCAGAAUAUGUUGUACAACAAGAAGGAGCAAAACUAAAUGUGGCAAUUGUAAGGCCAUCGAUUGUUGGUGCCAGUUGGAAAGAACCUUUUCCAGGAUGGAUUGAUAACUUUAAUGGACCAAGUGGUCUCUUUAUUGCGGCAGGGAAAGGAAUUCUUCGAACAAUACGUGCCUCCAACAAUGCCCUUGCAGAUCUUGUUCCUGUAGAUGUAGUUGUCAACAUGAGUCUUGCGGCAGCCUGGUAUUCCGGAGUUAAUAGGUAUAUGAGACCAAGAAACAUCAUGGUGUAUAAUUGUACAACAGGCAGCACUAAUCCUUUCCACUGGGGUGAAGUUGGAUAUUAUGUAAGUCAUUCCUUCAAGAUGAAUCCUUUAAACCAAGUAUUCAGGUGCCCCAGUUUUAAGUUUAAUUCCAACAGCCUAUCGCAUCAUUAUCGGAAGGGUGUCAGCCAUAGAGUAUCUGCAUUAUUGCUCGAUUGCACUCAUGUUGACAGGUCAGAAACCGCGGUAAGAAGAAUAGCAGUAAAUACACUAUGUAUUGGUAAGGUGGUGGCAGCUUGCUGGAGAGAUGAAAAAAAUCACUAGCAUGAGCUUUACCUUUAGAUUUACUCACCUGAUUAAUCACAAUCAGAAUGCUAGGACAUUUCUUAGAAUUUGGAGAUCUUUGGGGACACUAACUAUGGAUCACAUCGUAUUGGGUCGUUCAUCCUCCAAAAUUCCAUAAUAUAGGAAAUGUCCUACAUCAUGGUUGUCAUUGUUAUUAUAAGCUGAAAUUAAGCCCUUCUCUCCCUCUUAAAAACCUAGGGAUGAGUUUGUAUAGGGGAUUAAGGGCAAAAGUUUUGCUUCAAAUGGAUGGUGCAGUUUUAUGUGAAAAAUAUAGGAUGCUUCUAGAAAAUUACUUGAAAUAUCUCAGCUGCCCAUUCAGCUUAUAAUAUGGUUAUUUCAGUUUUUGACUAAUUAUCCAGGUUGGGAAUGGCAUAGUUAUGAAAAAAAAGUUAAUAAUAAACAGAAAACUUUGUUUUCUUAUCGUUGUUAUAGCUUUUCUUUCUUUUUUUUGUUGAAAUCCCGCAAACUUAAAGAUCUCCUACUGUCUUUACCACACAAUUACAGUGGAAUAUACUAUUAAAAUACUUAAUUUUUUUUAACUACAUUGGCAUUACAGUGGAGUCGUUGAUUGGAGAGUUCAGGAUUUGAGUAUUUUUGUAUAAAGAAGAUGCUGAUCCCAGAACUUCCAUCAACUACUCAAAAAAUAAAAGUGAGGUAACUGCCAGUUACAGUGUAUCAGGAUCUGAGUUCCUCGUAGGUAUUGUCUGUGGAUUCACUUUUCCAUGAUGUUUCUAACCCUAUAUGUUAGCUAAUUGAAAUAUGUGAGAGGUGUUGAACAACUUUAGAGCAGGUAAAGAAAUAUUUUCAGACUUUUCUAGAAUGAUCUGCAAAAUGCAAUACUUGCCAUUGGAAGCAUUCUUCAUGGCUAAAAUGCAGAUGUAAAUUCAUGAAUGGUGGCAGUGCAUGCUUUCUUUAUAUUAAUAAGGUUGUUAUAAUUUAGGACAGAAAAGUAAAAACUGGGUCAAAAAAAAAACAGGUUAAAUACAUCACAUUGCCUUACACGAAGAAAGAGGGCUUAGUAAAAUUUUAAAAAAAUAAGUGAAUAGCUGGUUUACUAAAUGCUUCAGAGGAGAUGUUGCUGCAUAACAAAUCAUCUCAAACUUAGAAGCUAAAAACAGCAACAGUUAUUUUAUUAUUUCUUUCAAUUAUUUCUGUCAGGAUCAAGAAUUUGAGAAAGAAUCCACUGGGCAGUUUUGGCUUGGAGUCUUUCAUGUGUUUGUGAUCAGAUGAAAGAGGCCGGUGGGCAGAGAGGCAAUGGAACAGCAAGGGGACUGAUGUUACUCUUUGUCGUGUCAUAAGGAUCUCUCCAUAUAGCUCUUUGCAAGGAUUAAUGAUAGCCUUAGGGGAAUUAGACUUCUUAUAUAGCAGCUGAUGGCUUCAAGGGGGAAGUCUUUUAGCAAGUAAGGUGGAGGCUGCGUUGCCUUUUCUGAGCUACCCAUGGAAGUCAUGCAGCAUCACUUUUGCCUCAUUCUUCUAGUUACAAGUGAGUCACAAAUCUUCUUAAAUUUUUUUUCAUAUGUUCAUAAUUUUAUUUUGGUGCCUGACAUAGCACAUUUUUUAAAAAUACUUCAAGUUCUAGGGUACGUGUGCACAACGUGCAGAUUUGUUACAUAUGUAUACUUGUGCCAUGUUGGUGUGCUGCACCCAUUAACUUGUCAUUUACAUUAGGUAUUUCUCCUAAUGGUAUCCCUCCCCCCUCCCCCCACCCCACGACAGGCCCCCAGUGUGUGAUAUUCCCCACCCUGUGUCCAAGUAAGGGGAUUUAGAAAGUGGUCAAGAUGAAGGGUAUUGUUGCCAUCAUUUUUGGAAAGUACAAUCUGCUAUAGUCAACCUUCUGGCCAAAACAAUUCAUAUUUCUUCUACAUGGAAAGGACAGUUGCUUCUUCCCCACUCAUCCUGCCUUCCCCCUCGCGCCUCCCCAUCCCCACCACCGCCCCAGAUCCCUGUGGCAUCAGCUGGAAGCCAGGGUUUUGUCAUCUAAAUCUGGUCAAUUGGCGGAUGACGCUCUUUAGGAGUGAUUUUGUCAGCAUAGCUCCUCAAGUAUAGUUCCUCAAUAAUUGAUAUGUGAACUAAAGCAACGAGUUACUGACUGCCCAUACGCCCAUCAUAAAUGAUGGUAAGCAUAGGAUAAUGGCUUUAGACAGUUUUAUUCAAAAAGAGAGAAAUUGGGAGGCACCCAGCAAACACUGGUCUAUAACAUUUCUGAAUUCCAGUCAGAUAUGUGUUGAUGAUUUCUUGAUAAGGAGCUCAGUCUUAUUCUCUGGGAGUUCUCUGAGGUUCUUGCCUCUGCCCUCUGAGUCAUCCUUCCUUUUGCAUAAAAACUGGCCUGUGGGCUCUGUGUGCAGCCAAGUAGCCUUCUUAUCCUGCUUCGUGCCCAUGAAAGGUUAGGGGAUCAGGGCAGGAACUGGAAAGCUUUUCUUGUAAAUUAAGGCCAUAUAGUAAAUAUUUUAGGUUUAGCAGGACAUGCGGUUUUUGUUGAAGCUACUCAUCUUUGCUGUUAAAAAUGAAAGCAGCCAUAGACAAUAGGCAAAUGAAUGAAUAUGACUGUGUCCCAGUAAAACUUUAUUUACAAAAACAGGUGGUGGGCUGGAUUUGGUAUAUAGGCUCUGGUUUGCUGACCCUUGAUAUAGCAGUCUCUUCAUUUUUUUUUUCUUGUCUAUCCCUUUACAUGUAAUCUGACAUGAUUGCUUAAAAAUUGUGUGAGUUUCCGGUGUAUCUGUUUUCAAGGAAUCCAGCCUAUUAGACGAAAGCCAUACCCAUAAGUUUCUUUGACACAAACCCUUCUCUAUCUUGGGUCCCCUGUGAGGUUCCUAUGGGACAGCACUUUUAGAUCUUAAAUCCUUGCCUCUUAGAUCCUGCCUUUUGAACAAUAAGAGUUUCUGUUACACAUUUCUUUAAGAUCUGGAGAGUGCCUUUUGUCUGUCUGAAAGUUCUGGAAGGCACUGCCUAGGUCUUUCUAAAGUCUUAGCAAAGGAUUCAUCUUCCCCUACCCUGCUAUGCUCAGAAACUGUUUCUUAAAGAAUUCCUGGCUGACAUUUUACAUUUCCUCCAAAUUCCACUCAAAUAGUUCAUUUUUUUAAGAUCAUCUUUGUCCUCUUUUGCCCUCUUUCAGCAAAUUUCUGCUAGAUCAUUGAGUUUAUUAGUACACUUUCUAUAUUCCAUAUAACCAGAGGUGACAGUUUGUUGUCCUCACUUCAAGCCCUCACCAACAGCUUUCUUAAAACCCUUUAAGGCUUCCAUUAAUAAUGUUUUCCUGGUCCUUUCACAUUUCACUACUGAUCACCUCACAGGCCUUAGAGAUUUUGUUUACCACUUGACCCUGAAGCCAAUACCACAUGUUUUAGGUUUUUAUUAUAGCAGCCCCUCCCAGUGUUGAGAUCUGUGUUGAGAUUUGUUAAUCUGUUUUACAUAACAAGUCACCUCAAACUUAGUGUCUUAAAGCAAUCAUUUUAUUUGUGUGUCACAAUAUCUGUGGGUCAGGAAUUCUAGAAGGGUUAGCUUGAUGGUAAUGGCUCAGGAUCUUUCAAAUGAUUGUAGUCAGACAGGGACUGGAGGAACUUUGCUGUGGAGGGAGUGGUAAAGGGGGGAAGGGGACAGAGUAGCUGGGGUGGCUGGGCAUCUCUCUCUCUCCAGUAGUGUCAUACCCUCUCCAUGUGGCCUCUCCAUAUGGACUAGUUUGAGCUUCCUCGCAGUAUGGCAGCCUCAGGGGGAGUUGGACAGCAUACACAGUGACUGAAGGCUUCAAGGGUGAGUAUUCAGUGAGCAAGACAGAAAGCUCUACACCUUUCUGACCUAGCCUCGGAAGUCACAUCAUGUCACUUCCACCUCAUUCUGUUGGUUCUAAGUUAUUUUCAACUCUCAUUGAGAAGACAGUCAAGGUGACAUUGUAUUGUAGGUGGGCAUGUAGGAUGGAGAUAAUAUCAUAGGCACCUUUGGAAAUUAAUAUCUUUCCUAAAUAGGAAACGUUAAGGAAACAGUCUUCUUAACUGAGGUUUGUGCUGUGUGAGGCUUUCUAAGUAUCAAAGCAGGACAGAUCCUUGACCUCCGGGAGCUUAUAAUCUGAAUGCAACAAGGAAUAUAAAGGUUUUUUUACUUAGACAAUUUUGUAAAUGUUAAAUACAAAGUCUUAUAAUUUAUAAUAUUUCAUUUGUUCAGAAAUUUAUUGAGCACAGUAAUAGACUUUACACCUUAUAUUGGGGCCUUACUAUGAUGCCUAAUUCUACAUUAAACUGAUGUCAGUCAUGUCAUUCAUUUCAUCCAGUUUACUUGUUUACAUAAUAAUUCUGAAUGUGAGCUAGAUAAGCAUCUGACCUGACAUUUUUUAAAAAAUGGCUCCAUGAUCUUAUGUUUUGGUUAACUAGCAUAACUUUAUCUAGCUUAACUUCUCUAAACCAGGUAUCUAUUUUUAAUCUGUGUACUUCUCAGCUGGAGACAUUUGACAACAUUUGCAGGUAUUUUUAGUUAUCACAACAGGGGGAGGGCUGCUACCAGCACCUAGAGGCCAGGGAUGGUGACAAGCAUCUUAUAGCAUGCAAGAUAGCCCUCCACACGAAAGAAUGAUCAGACCCACAAUAUUUAUAGUGCCAAGGUUGAGAAACCCUGGACUAGAUAAUCAUUAAGAUCUUGCCUUACUCUAAAGGAUUGUGAUUAUUUUUUUAAGUUGCCAUAAUAAAGAAUAAAUACAUAUUCAGAACAUACCUGGCAAUGUAGUCAUAAACAUCUGUUCUAAGGUAUGUUUAACCAAGGAGUGAUGGUGCAAAGUUUUACAUUUCUUAUUCCCCAAUAGUUUUCAAUCCAGUAUUUUUGUUGCAUGAUAAAUAUUCUAUAAAUUUCACACACAAAUAUAUGGCCUUUCAAAUUUCUUCCCCCUCCCCGAUUUUUUAUUGCAAUUAUUUUUUGAAUGGCUGAAUUACUGAUUGAUGUUAGGGUGAUUGUGUCACUUGAAUGAAUCUGAAGAUAAGAUUAGGUGAGAGAAUUAUCAGUGAACAAGAGUUAAGAAAAACUUUUUAAUAAGGUAUAUAUAGGAAAACCGUGUUAGCUGUGUGUGUGUGUGAGAUUUAAGUAUGCUAAACUGGCGUGAUAGUAUAUAUUGAUGUAGUGACAAACUUGUUGUAUCUUUUUGUUUAGAAAAAAAUAAUCACCUAAUCUUUUCUAAGAGCAGCAUGUGUUUUUCCCCCAGAUGCUUUUUAUCUACAGAACUAUCCCUGUCCAGAAAUUGCCUUAGAUGCUUGAUAAUUCGUUUUGUGUUUGAGAUUUUAUUUUGAAGUUACUUUAUUGGAUGAAAUAUAGUUUUUUUUUACAUAGUUUAUAUUGCUUCAUUUUCUUCCAGUAUUCUGGAUUCAGAGUUUAUUUCUAAAUGUAUUGAAUUGUGUUAUCAGAAGUGCUUAGCUAAUGAUACUUUUUUGAUUUUUUUCUCCUUAUUUCUAAUGUAAUUUCCCUCCAUGCCCCUC